GGUUUACACAGUGUCACCCAAGCGACUGGGAGCCGCGUCCUGCUCUGGGACUGAGCCGUUGGAGCUGCCCCGCUGACCGCACUAGGCUGACCGCAACCGGCUGACCACACACAGUCCUCACUCCCCUGGCCCUGGUGGGCGGCAGGCACCAUGGCGCAGACAGUGCCGCCCUGCGAGCUGCCCUGCAAAGAGUACGACGUGGCCCGUAACACGGGCGCCUACACGUCCUCCGGCCUGGCCACCGCCAGCUUCCGCACCUCCAAGUACCUGCUGGAGGAGUGGUUCCAGAACUGCUAUGCUCGCUACCACCAGGCCUUCGCCGACCGCGACCAGUCGGAGCGGCAGCGGCACGAGAGCCAGCAGCUGGCCACAGAGACCCAGGCGCUGGCGCAGCGCACGCAGCAAGACUCCACGCGCACAGUGGGCGAGCGACUGCAGGACACGCACAGCUGGAAGUCGGAGCUGCAGCGUGAGAUGGAGGCGCUGGCUGCGGAGACCAACUUGCUCCUGGCCCAGAAGCAACGGCUGGAGCGCGCCCUGGACGCCACAGAGGUGCCCUUCUCCAUCACCACUGACAACCUGCAGUGCCGUGAGCGCCGCGAGCACCCCAACCUCGUGCGCGACCAUGUGGAAACGGAGCUGCUGAAGGCCCUUCCCCCUGCACUCUCUCAGUGCCUCAAGAACUCCUGCAGCUCCCGCAAACUCUCUGCCCGCAACAAGGGCACCUGCCAACUGAUGGAGACACUGACAGUGCACGGAGAGGCAAACCCAGGGAUAGAGGGGCGCAGGACCCGGGCCCUGGCACACAAGGAAGUACCCAGUGGUUGAGGCAAAGACCCCAAUCACAGAGAAAAGGCUUGUUCCUACACACAGCAAAUUAAACUGGCCAGGCAAUAAGAAGAAACACAGGGUCCUUCUCCUGUUCUUGGUGUGAAGAUGGCCUUUCCCAGCACAGAGCCCUGAGGGGCAGCCUGGGCGGGCAUCUGGGCCCCCAGAGUUUGGGUCCUCAGGGGCUGUCCAGAGGCCAAGGGCAGGCCAACGUUCCCAGGUGCACUGAGUGAGCAGCAGCGAUGACUCCUGAAGCCUGGGGCGUGGGAACUGCCGCUGAGGGACCUUCCCAGCAGCCCACAGAAGGCCCUGGAGGAAAACACCCCACUUACAACGCACCAAGGAGAAUGCCCAAAAGCCCAAGAUAAACCCAGUGAGAGAGCAGAACUUACACAGUCAGAGCUCAGGCCCGGCAUUCAACUCCUUGUGGUUGCUCAGGUGUUGACCAAGGCCUGCAGCAGCUGGGCCUCCUGGGAUCCUCACCAGGGACUGGCUCUGGUGCUCAGGGCGUCUCCUCCCUCAGGAAGCCGAGCUCAUCCGGAACAUUCAGGAGCUGCUGAAGAGAACCAUCAUGCAAGCAGUGAGCCAGAUCCGACUGAACCGGGAGCACAAGGAGACCUGCGAGAUGGACUGGUCAGACAAGAUGGAGGCCUACAACAUCGACGAGACCUGCGGGCGCCACCACAGCCAGAGCACCGAGGUGCAGGCUCAUCCGUACUCCACCACCUUCCAAGAGAGCGCCUCCACCCCGGAGACCCGGGCCAAGUUCACGCAGGACAAUCUGUGCCGUGCCCAGCGCGAGCGCCUGGCCUCGGCCAACCUGCGGGUGCUGGUGGACUGCAUCCUUCGCGACACCUCCGAGGACCUGCGGCUCCAGUGCGACGCCGUGAACCUGGCCUUCGGGCGCCGCUGUGAGGAGCUGGAGGACGCGCGGUACAAGCUGCAUCACCACCUGCACAAGACACUGCGGGAAAUCACAGAUCAGGAACACAACGUGGCGGCACUGAAGCAGGCCAUCAAGGACAAAGAGGCACCUCUGCACGUAGCCCAGACCCGGCUGUACCUGCGCUCGCACCGGCCCAACAUGGAGCUGUGCCGUGACGCAGCCCAGUUCAGGCUGUUGAGUGAGGUGGAGGAGCUGAACAUGUCCCUCACAGCACUGCGAGAGAAGCUUCUAGAAGCGGAGCAGUCCCUGCGCAACCUCGAGGACAUCCACAUGAGCCUGGAGAAGGACAUUGCCGCCAUGACCAACAGUCUCUUCAUCGACCGCCAGAAGUGCAUGGCCCAUCGUACUCGCUACCCCACCAUCCUGCAGCUGGCUGGCUACCAGUGAGCAGCGGCACGGUGCUUCCCCCCAGUCCCCCAAAUAAACAGCGCGUUAGCUUUC